GUCCUCCGGGGAUUAGAGCCGGUGGGCUCGUUGUGGGCGCCAUUUCUCGGCGUCUACCGAGGAGCCGCCCCUUUCUCAGCCUUGCUCGGCUCUUCCCCGCUCUGGUCGCCGGGGCUGCGCCGUCCCCAGCUCAGGUAAGCGCGAGGCCCGGCGGCGGCGCCGCAGUACAGUCCGCUGCGCUCCUAGCCGAGUGGACCCUUCCUCGCCCGCGCCUGCGGUAGCGGCCUUGUCCCCGGGGAGGCGGGCGGGGGCCGCACCCAGACCCUAGGGCGGCCGGCCCCUCUCUCGUCGGGCCGGCAGGGCAUUAAUCCCGCCGGAGGGAGGGGCGGCGGCGGCCAAUGAGGCAGGGCCGCCGAGUUUCGGUCGAUACCGCGCGACGGGCCGGGGCGGAGGGCCCGGGGCAGCCGGGUUAAUGUUUGCCGAGCGGACGCGCUCCCCGAGCCGCGGGUACCCCUCGCUGGUCCGCUGGGCUGCCGUCCAGCGGGAGAGACAAAAGUCGCAAGGGAAGGGGAAAAACGAACUGAGUUUGUGUCACUGUCUUGGUGGACUUUUCGAGCUAACCUGUAUUUGAGAAAAACUUCAGUCUCUUGGGAAAGGAGAGGCAGUGACAAAAAUGCUGAGUUUCUUCCGUAGAACACUAGGGCGUCGGUCUAUGCGUAAACAUGCAGAGAAGGAACGACUCCGAGAAGCACAACGCGCCGCCACACAUAUUCCUGCAGCUGGAGAUUCUAAGUCCAUCAUCACGUGUCGGGUGUCCCUUCUGGAUGGUACUGAUGUUAGUGUGGACUUGCCAAAAAAAGCCAAAGGACAAGAGUUGUUUGAUCAGAUUAUGUACCACCUGGACCUGAUUGAAAGCGACUAUUUUGGUCUGAGAUUUAUGGAUUCAGCACAAGUAGCACAUUGGUUGGAUGGUACAAAAAGCAUCAAAAAGCAAGUAAAAAUUGGUUCACCCUAUUGUCUGCAUCUUCGAGUUAAGUUUUAUUCCUCAGAACCAAAUAACCUUCGUGAGGAGCUAACCCGGUAUUUAUUUGUUCUUCAGUUAAAACAAGAUAUUCUCAGUGGAAAAUUAGACUGUCCCUUUGAUACAGCAGUGCAAUUGGCAGCUUAUAAUCUGCAAGCUGAACUUGGUGACUAUGAUCUUGCUGAGCAUAGUCCUGAACUUGUCUCAGAGUUCAGAUUCGUGCCUAUUCAGACUGAAGAGAUGGAACUGGCUAUUUUUGAGAAAUGGAAGGAAUACAGAGGUCAAACACCAGCACAGGCUGAAACCAAUUAUCUGAAUAAAGCCAAAUGGCUAGAAAUGUAUGGGGUUGAUAUGCAUGUGGUCAAGGCUAGAGAUGGGAAUGACUAUAGUUUGGGACUAACACCAACAGGAGUCCUUGUUUUUGAAGGAGAUACCAAAAUUGGCUUAUUUUUUUGGCCGAAGAUAACCAGAUUGGAUUUUAAGAAGAAUAAAUUAACCUUGGUGGUUGUAGAAGAUGAUGAUCAGGGCAAAGAACAGGAACAUACAUUUGUCUUUAGACUGGAUCAUCCAAAAGCAUGCAAACAUUUAUGGAAAUGUGCUGUGGAGCAUCAUGCUUUCUUCCGCCUUCGAGGCCCCGUCCAAAAGAGUUCUCAUCGAUCAGGAUUUAUUCGACUAGGAUCACGAUUUAGAUAUAGUGGGAAAACAGAGUAUCAGACCACAAAAACCAAUAAAGCAAGAAGAUCAACAUCCUUUGAAAGAAGGCCCAGCAAACGAUAUUCUAGACGAACUCUACAAAUGAAAGCAUGUGCUACAAAACCUGAAGAACUUAGUGUUCACAAUAAUGUUUCGACCCAAAGUAAUGGCUCCCAACAGGCUUGGGGGAUGAGAUCUGCUCUGCCUGUGAGUCCUUCCAUUUCCUCUGCUCCUGUGCCAGUGGAGAUAGAGAAUCUUCCACAGAGUCCUGGAACAGACCAGCAUGACAGGAAAUGCAUUCCUCUGAAUAUUGAUUUGCUGAAUAGCCCAGACUUAUUGGAAGCAACGAUUGGUGAUGUAAUUGGGGCAUCUGACACUAUGGAAACAUCCCAAGCACUGAAUGACGUUAAUGUAGCCACCAGGCUUCCGGGAUUAGGGGAACCUGAAGUUGAAUAUGAGACAUUAAAAGACACCUCAGAGAAGCUCAAACAGCUUGAGAUGGAGAACAGUCCUUUGCUGUCCCCUCGAUCCAACAUCGAUGUUAACAUAAACAGCCAGGAGGAAGUGGUGAAGUUGACUGAGAAAUGCCUUAAUAAUGUCAUUGAGAGCCCAGGAUUGAAUGUCAUGAGAGUUCCUCCUGACUUCAAGAGUAACAUUUUGAAGGCUCAAGUAGAAGCAGUGCAUAAGGUUACAAAAGAAGAUAGCUUAUUAAGUCAUAAAAAUGCCAAUGUUCAGGAUGCUGCCACAAACAGUGCUGUGUUAAAUGAGAAUAAUGUGCCCCUCCCCAAAGAGUCUCUUGAGACUCUGAUGCUUAUCACACCUGCCGACAGUGGUUCUGUUCUAAAGGAAGCUACAGAUGAAUUGGAUGCCUUGCUUGCAUCUCUAACUGAGAAUCUAAUUGAUCACACAGUUGCACCUCAGGUGUCUUCCACAUCCAUGAUCACACCCCGGUGGAUUGUUCCGUUGUGUGUGUAUCUCCCACAGCAGAGUGGUGCCAUGUCUAAUGGACUUGCGGGAUGUGAAAUGCUUUUGACAGGGAAGGAGGGACAUGGUAAUAAAGAUGGAAUCUCACUGAUCUCUCCCCCAGCGCCAUUCUUGGUAGAUGCUGUGACCAGCUCUGGUCCCAUUUUGGCAGAAGAAGCUGUCCUGAAGCAGAAGUGUUUACUGACCACUGAGCUCUGAGGGCCUGUAGCUGGAAUACGCAUCUCUCCAGCAUUCCGUCCUGGGAUCCGUUUCAGCUAGAAUAUGUUGGAUUCAGGAGCUUGUCCAUUAUUUGUAGGUAAAAAAAGCUGCACGUAGAUUUGACUUCAACUCCGUAAAAAAGACAGCUGUAUUUUCCGUCCAACUGGAAUUGUUGAAUCACACUGCAUAGCUGCCCAAAAGAGAGUGUUUGGUCUUGAACUUUCUAUACUUUUAUAAAUGUUACAAAUUCCCGAAAGAAGGGAAUUUCUUUUUCUGGGGUUUCCUUCAAACUCUUGGCUCCACCUAGCGGUUCUAUUUGUUCAUAACAACUUCAUAACAAGCCUGCCUCUGGUAGUCAACAGCCUUUUGAAAGCUAUUUCCAUCUAGUAUCAGGGUGAGAGCAUCCUUGAUCUGGCUGCCUGUUAGAGAAAUUGCACUUUUCCUGACUUACCUAGAAAUCAAGAAUUUAGGAAAUUAAUGUGGACACUAUAAAGGCAGACUUAGGGCCAACUUUUUUUUUUUUUUACAAUUAUUACAACACUAAAGAGAAGUUUAGAAUAUAGAGAGUUUUUAAAUGUCUCCCAUUCUUUUGAUUUCUUACUGUACUGGCUAUCUUAAUAUUUCAAGUUUACAUCAAGAUAAACCCUGAGAAGAACUACGGAGAAAUCAAAUAAAAUCCUGUCAUAUUUUUUUCACCCUGCCUUUCCACAGGAAGCACUCACAGGCACCACACACGUAUCAUGUAACUUAUCAGUGGGGUGGGUUACUGUUGAAGAGACCCUGGGGCAUUUACCUCAGGCAUCUGCACUCCUCCGAGCCCGGUGGAGAAUGCAGGCUGCUGUAGUCUCAGGUAAUGAAGGCACAGCACAGCAGUACUCCACAUUGUUUCCUAUUUGGACAUAGACUUCAUUUCCUUUCAGUAUAAGCUGAAUAAAUUUAGAGCUUUCAAACUGGAAAAAAAAAUGAAACAAAACAAAUACACCAAGACCAAAAUAGGCAAUAGGAACAGGGGUGAAGGGAUGUUGUUUCUUAAAUACCUACCAUGUAUGAAGCUAUACACAGCAUAUACCGAAAGAACCUGCAUUGCACUAGGAAUUCUGUGUUAGUUUAAAAGAGAUCUCUAAAACUUCCCCAUCCCUUUGGGCCUGUACAAAGAAAUUCUGGAUGUUAAAAUAAUAUAUACUCAUCACAGAAAAAUAAAGUAUAGCAAUGUCCAUCUGUAAUUCUAAUACCCAGAAAUAACGCUAUUUAGCUUUAUAAUUUUCGAAUGAACAAGGUAAACCUCGGUUGCCAUGGGGAAGAAGGAUGAUGUGGAAACCAUAUUGGUAAAGUUGUUAAUCCCUCGUUAUGGAGAACUGAUCUUAAGCUAUACCUCCUGGAAUUUGCUUUCUAGUUUUCUGUCCUGCAAUAUGUAUAUAAUUAAGCACUAAUUUGUACUGCUUAGCAUAAAAGAACAUCCAGUCUUAGAUCCUUAAAACUUCAUGGAUUGGACUUUCCUGGGCUCCUUAUAACAUAAUCGUGUGUCCAGGCAAACGCACACUAGUGUCUGACUGGAAAGCUCAGGAAUUUUAAUCUUGCACUGUUUCCCAGGGAGCUGUAGUGAUUGGAACCCACGUUUGCACAAAACAUUUUUGCAGAAGGAAAGUCAACACUUCUUGCUGGCUGCCUCCCCUUAGCCAUUAUGCUAAAAACAGCUUCUGAGUUUCACUGGUGGGGCUCUUGCCAGUUCUUAAUUAUAGGACAUAUUUUCUCAAAGCUGAAGGUGACACCUAGAACCAGGGGCUUGACCCAGGACAUGAUGGAAUGAGCAUCAAAUUUUCAGUGUCUUGGCAACCGUAGAUGUCCUACAGGGUUACCGUUGUGCUGCUCACCACAGAGCAGCUGAGGCAUUAUGCCUUGGAAGACCUAAAUCUCCCAUCCAGUUCAGGAGGUGACAACAUCCUUAUUUUAAACUUCCUAAAAUUAGGAAUUAGGUAGUUGGACAUAGUCUGUGACCUUUAUGUCGUUGGAUACCUGUAUUCUUGACAGUUAGAAUAUUGGUAGGGACUUUGUUAAAAUUCACUUGAAUUUCAAGCUCAGAGGAAACUUUGUCUCAUGCCCUGACAUGAAGUGGCAAACACGGAAGUUCAUACUUGAAUGCUGAAUUGGCCCCGACAGAUUAAAUGCGUGUUGGGGAUUGGUUUCCUGUCAUAGCUGCUGCUGCUGCCAUGCGCAGAGCUGCUGUAACAGCUCUUCCUGUUCUGCUCCCCUGAGAACAGUGUGGUGGGGAGAGGCAGGGCUGAGGUGGUCUACGAAUGUGGCAGGUAGGGAAGGGGAGAUGUCUGUCUCUUGAGAAGAGAGAGGCAUGUGUGCCGGCAUCCUUGAUGGGUUCAAAGAGAAAGGUUGGAGAUGAUAGUGGGUGAGAAGCAGGCUGGUGAGACUGGGCUGAGGUUGGAGAAGGGGCAGCCGGGGGCACUGCUGAGGGUUUGCCGUGCACGCCUCGGACGGAGCACGGUGGGGUGGCGGGGAGCAGAUAGUGCUGCCUCCCUGCGGGCAGACAGGAGAGGAACCUCAACUCAGUCCAUUUCAUAGCCCUGAUAGGGGAAGUGGGAGUUGACAGGAUGGUUUAAAAUAAGACGUGAAGGUUUCAGUUACCUGCUCUAGACUUUGCCUGAGAACUUGUAAAUUAAUCAGUGAGACCUAAUUUGUGACAUGUCAGUAGCAUCAUCUUUUGACACACAGGAGGUCAUGGUCAUUUCAUUCCUACUCUUCAGGAGACACUGCUGAACAGAGGAAUGAUUCUGUUCCUUGUGUGCUUACUUCCUUAACAUUUAUACAUUGUUUUAAGAAAAAACUUUUAAAAAUAUUUCUUAUAGUCUCCUAACAUUUGUCUCUAGCCUUUGCCUUUGUACAAUCACAGAUAUCCUAUGGAGAUUUAAGGAUGAAAGCCCUGAGUUGUUCUUGGGUUCUUGGAUCUGGACUACUUGUUAUCUUAUGCUUCUCACUUCUGGCUAAAACUUGCACCUCUUCUUCUCUUAGCUAAGCCCCAAAAUGAAGAUUUCCUUCAGAAGUCUUGUUAGCAGAAUUAUUUAUCAGUCACAGAGAGAAAAAUCUGCUAUUUUUCUAAGUAAGAGUCUCGAGAAGCAGAGUUUUUGUCUUGUCAUUGAGAGGAGUCAGCAGUCUUGUUCUGUAAAGGACCAGAGAUGGUAAAUACUGUCCCACUCAGCUCUGCUGGCGCAGUACAGCAGCAGCAGCCCCAGCACAGCUGUGUUCCUGCGGAGUCCCCUUUACAAAGCCGCUGACCCCUGAUGUGAAACUUUGUAGAGCAGCAGAGUGGCUGCGUGAAACGGGAGGCUGGCAGGUCCUCAGAUAGGUUCUGCAGUGUUACCUGUCACUUGGAGGCAGCCAACACUUCUGGACAUUGCAUCCUUAUUCACACAUGUGGCAGCUGAACGAGGUGCUGUUGUGGGUGUCUCAGCUCUGAGGGUCUUUGUGAGCUCCCACUGUUGUGGGUGUCUCAGCUCUGAGGGUCUUUGUGAGCUCCCACUGUUGUGGGUGUCUCAGCUCUGAGGGUCUUUGUGAGUUCCCACCAACUUUUAAUUAUUCAUGCCCUUGACCAUGUGGUUGCUUGGAGACCUGGGGUCUUCUGCAGACUGAAGAAGACACAUUUCUAGAUUAUUUGUCCUUUUUAUCCUCUCAAAAAUUUAAACACUGUACCUCUUCAGUGGUCAGAAGAAAGUUGGAAACUUUUCCUACAUAUUAGGCGUUAGUAUGAGGACAUUUGUUUGAAUUAUAGAAAUUUGCCCUGAGCUGAACUGGGUUGUGUUAACACAUUGGUAGAGCUAUGAUUCCUUCCCAGUUCUAAGAGAUACGAUCUGUAAGUCCCUAUGUCACCACAUUGCUUGAGAUGAUCAUUCAGUUACUUGUCAGGAUUUCUCCUCUUCAGAGAGAUUUUUUUUUAUAGCACAGAUUCCUUUGCCCCUUUUAUCUCCUUAUCUGGAUAUGAUAAGUGGUUAUGAGGGUCUCACUAACUAUUUUGUGUUUACCUUUUAUAUGUGUAAAACUUUGCAGUAGCAUUUAAAGUGUAAUUUAUUUUUCUAUCAAGUGCACUAUUCAUUUAGUGUGUUCCAGUUUUAUAUGACUUGUAUUAGAAACACUGCACUGAGUUGUUUGUACACUGAAAUGAGAACUCUAGAUGUAACUCUAUUCAAAUAAACCUUCGUGAGACAUUCA